GCGGCACAGCUAGGGCAUCCCGGCGAGGAGCGCCGCCAGGCCCCGGGGUAGGACUUGGGGUGCGGUGUCGGUGCGGCCGCCGAGGGGGGCUGAUUGCAUGCAAUUCGGGGCAUACACACAGACCGCGGGGUCUCCGGGAUAUCGGGGCUAUCAAGGACGGGCUGGGGGAUGGGGACUUGGGGACGGGGCCCAGGGAUGGUGAAGACGGGGGUGCGGCUGGCAGAAUCAGGGCAGGCAGAGGCUGCGCGCCGCGGAGGCUGCUGGUCCCUGACGCCUUGACCCUUCCUCUCCCGCAGCCACAGCCGGGCCUGGCGGGGGGACCAUGGGCGCCUCGGUCUCCAGGGGCCGGGCCGCCCGGGUCCCCGCGCCGGAGCCGGAACCCGAAGAGGCGCUGGACCUGAGCCAACUACCCCCAGAGCUGCUUCUGGUGGUGCUGAGCCACGUCCCCCCGCGCACGCUGCUCGGGCGCUGCCGCCAAGUGUGCCGGGGCUGGCGAGCCCUGGUGGACGGCCAGGCCCUGUGGCUGCUGAUCCUGGCCCGCGACCACGGCGCCACCGGCCGCGCGCUGCUGCACCUCGCCCGCAGCUGCCAGUCUCCCGCCCGUAACGCCAGGCCUUGCCCCCUGGGCCGCUUCUGCGCGCGCAGACCCAUCGGACGCAACCUUAUUCGCAACCCCUGCGGCCAAGAAGGCCUCCGAAAGUGGAUGGUGCAACACGGUGGGGACGGCUGGGUGGUGGAGGAAAACAGGACAACCGUGCCUGGGGCCCCUUCUCAGACGUGCUUCGUGACUUCAUUCAGCUGGUGUUGCAAGAAGCAGGUCUUGGACCUAGAGGAGGAGGGUCUGUGGCCAGAACUGCUGGAUAGUGGCAGGAUUGAGAUUUGUGUCUCUGACUGGUGGGGAGCCCGACACGACAGCGGCUGUAUGUACAGACUCCUCGUCCAACUUCUAGACGCCAACCAGACUGUUCUAGAUAAAUUCUCUGCUGUGCCUGAUCCCAUCCCGCAGUGGAACAACAAUGCCUGCCUUCACAGACACAGUUUCACUAUGUUGCCUGGGCUGGUCUUGAACUCCUGUGCUCAAGCAAUCCUCUCGCCUCAGCCUCCCACAGUGCUGGGAUUACAGGCACAAGCCACUGCAUCCAGCCCGUGCGUGUUUUUGAGUGCACCAAUUCCAGCUCUAAGAUUGACGAGAUCCUACUGGCCUGGACCUGACUGUAAGCCAAAACCUGAUACUGCUGUCUGCUCUGUGCUGUUUCAGUCUCAGCAUGUGCUGUGCUAAAUUAAAAACGGGCGCACACUCCAGGAACAGCACUUCGACUAUGAGACCAUUGCAGACUUAGGGCACCCUCCGUGGGACCUAAACUGAAAACAUCAUGGAUGCUGACUGGACCAUCUGGAUCACAUAAAAAUGCCCACAGGAAAGGGCUUCUUUUUGUUUUUUGAGACGGAGUCUCACUGUCUCCCCCAGGCUGGAGUGCAGUGGCGUGAUCUCAGCUCACUGCAAGCUCUGCCUCCCAGGUUCACGCCAUUCUCCUGCCUCAGCCUCCCGAGUAGCUGGGACUACAGGCGCCCACCACCACACCCGGCUAAUUUUUUGUAUUUUUAGUAGAGACGGGGUUUCACCGUAUUAGCCAGGAUGGUCUCGAUCUCCUGACCUCGUGAUCCGCCUGCCUUGGCCUCCCAAAGUGCUGGGAUUACAGAUGUGAGCCACCACGCCAGGCCAAGGAAAGGGCUUCUUCUUUGAGGAAACCAUCUACAAUCAACUGGCUUCUUGGCUCUAUAUUUCUUUCUUUUUAUUUUCUUUUAUUUUUUUUAAUUUUUUUUUAGACGGAGUCUCCUUCUGUCACCCAUGCUGGAGUGCAGUGGUGUGAUCUCAGCUCACUGCAACCUCCACCUCCUGGGUUCAAGCAAUUCUCCUGCCUCAGCCUCCCAAGUAGCUGGGAUUACAGGCAUACGCCACCAUGCCUGGCUAAUUUUUGUAUUUUUAGUAGAGACGGGGCUUCACCAUGUUGGCCAGGCUGGUUUCGAACUCCUGACCUCAGGUGAUCCUCCCGCCUCAGCCUCCCAAAGUGCUGGGAUUGCAGGCAUGAGCCACCGCGCCUGGCCAUCGAAUGUAUUUCUAACCUGUGAUUCCUGCCAAAAGCUGUAAGUUCAAGGAGGGCACCUCUCAGGGACUGUGACCCCUCUGGCUGCUUCUGACAGGUUGGACACUUGGGAGACGCCUCAUUUCUGUUGCCUUGUGCUCAACUUUCUGGAUUAGUUGUAGGUUGCAACUGUGGCCUGUAGCCUGACUCUACUUCCCCACUUCUCUCCUGCUACAACACACACCUUAGGAAGGCAGUUUGAUUACUGAUGCAGCGGUCCCCAGAAAGGGAUUGAGCUUUUGCAGGAAGUUCAUUGGAUGAUGAUCGGGAAAGAGGUUAUAGAAAAACAUUUUGAAAAUUUAGGAUUUCUGUUGUUUGUUUGUUCGUUUGUUUGUUUGUUUGUUUGUUUUGAGACAGGGUCUCACUCUGUUGCCCAGGCUGGAGUGCAGUAGCGCCAUCUUGACUCACUGCAACCUCUACCUCCCAGGUUCAAGCAAUUGUCCUGCCUCAGCCUCCCAAGUACCUAGGACUACAGGCCCGCGCCUCCACGUCUGGCUAAUUUUUGUAUUUUUUUAGUAGAGUCGGGGUUUCACUCUGUUGGCCAGGCUGGUCUCAAACUCCCAACCUCAGGUGAUCCGGCCUCCUCGGCCUCCCAAAGUGCUAGCAUUACAGGCAUGAGCAAUCGUGCCCCGCUUCUUUUCUUGAUAUAUAAGCUGGUAACAAACAAAAAAAAAGAAGAAAAUUUAGAAUUUCAUCCUGACCAAUUCCUGGAUGUGAUGUGUGUUUCUAGUCAACUUGUAUAAAAAUGUUUCUUCUGUGAAAUGCUUCCAUCCCUUUUGUAUCCAACCCUUCUGGAUGAAACAUUUAGAUGAGAAUUUGAAAAUGACGCUGGGCGUGGUGGCUCACGCCUGUAAUCCCAACACUUUGGGAGGCCGAGGUGGGUGGAUCUCCUGAGGUCGGGAGUUUGAGACCAGCCUGGUCAACAUGGAGAAACCCCAUCUCUAUUAAAAAUACAAAAUGGGUCGGGCGUGGUUGCCCAUGCCUGUAAUCGCAGCUACUCGGAAGGCUGAGGCAGGAGAAUUGCUUGAACCCGGGAGGCUGAGGUUGCGGUAAGCAAAGAUCACGCCAUUGCACUCCAGCCUGGGCAACAAGAGCGAAACUGUCUCAAAAAAAAAAAAAAAGGUUAAUAAAUUCAGGACAUUUUUGGGAUACAAAUCAAUAUUGAAAAUCAGGGCUCGGCCGGGCGUGGUGGCUCACGCCUGUAAUCCCAGUACUUUGGGAGGCCGAGACGGGCGGAUCACGAGGUCAGGAGAUCGAGACCAUCCUGGCUAACAUGGUGAAACCACGUCUCUACCAAAAAAAAAAUACAAAAAAUUAGCUGGUCAUGGUGGCGGGCACCUGUAGUCCCAGCUACUCGGGAGGCUGAGGCAGGAGAAUGGCGUGAACCCGGGAGGUGGAGCUUGCAGAGAGCCGAGAUUGCGUCACUGUACUCCAGCCUGGGAUGACAGAAAGAGACUCCGUCUAAAAAAAAAAAAAAAAAAAGAAAAGAAAAUCAGGGCUCAGCAUAGUGGCUUAUGCCUAUAAUUCUCAACACUUUGGGAGGCGAGGUGGGAGGAUUGCUUGAGGCCAAGAGUUCAAGACCAGCCGGGGCAACAAAGGGAGACCCCCCCUCCCCCGCCGCCAUCUCUGCGAAAAAUAAGAAAAGAAAAUUAGUUGUAUUUCAAUACACUAGCAAUGCCAAUCUGAAAAUGAAAUUAAGAAAACAAUUCUACUUUUACACUGAAAGCUACAAUAUUGCUGAAAGAAAUUAAAUAAGAGCUAAAUAAAUAGAUACCCCAUGUUCAUCAACUGGAAGACUUUAUAUUUUUAAGAUGACAAUACUCCCUAAAUUGAUCUACAGAUUCAGUUGCAAUGCCUAUCAAAAAAAAAUUGUUUUGAGAGAGAGAGUUUCGCUCUGUUGCCCAGGGUGGAGUCCAGCGGCACAGUCUCAGCUCACUGCAACCUCCGCCUCCCAGGUUCAAGCAAUUCUCAUGCCUCCACCUUCCAGGUAGCUGGGAUUACAGGCGGGUGACACCACGCCCGGCUAAUGUUUUGUAUUUUUAGUAGAGACGGGGUUUCACCAUGUUGCCCAGGGUGGUCUCAAACUCCUGACCUCGGGUGGUCCGCCCUCCUCAGCCUCCCAAAGUGCUGGGAUUACUGGCGUGAGCCACUGCACCCGGCCACUUGUCAAAAUUUUAAGAGCCAUUUUUUUUGCAGAAAUGGACAAGCUGAUCUCAAAAUUCACAUGGAAUUGCAAGAGGUUCCAAAUAGCCAAAACAAUCUUGAAAAAGAACAAAGUUGGAGGAUUCACGCUUUCCAGUUUCAAAACUUACUACAAAGCUACAGUAAUCAGAACAGUGUGGUCCUGGCAUAAGUAAUGUUGGACAAGUGAGCCCCAAAGUGAGACUUAGCCCAUGAGGUUCUUGGCUUUGCCCAGGAAAGAAUUCAAGGCCAAGCCAAUGGUAGAAGAAAACAGCUUUAUUGAAGGGGCAGUGUUAUAGCUCCAGCCCUGUUACAACUCUGAUUACUCCUGCACAGCAGGGCUCUGGCAGAGACUAGCAGCUCAGGGCAGUUUUGCAGUCAUUUAUAUCUACUUUAAACACAUGCAGAUUAAGGGGUGAUUUGUGCAAAAAUUUCUAGGGAAUGGGUAAUAACUUUUGGGUCAUCGAGUCAAUGCCAUGGAAGAGACGGGGGAUAACCCCCUGGUGUUGCGAUGGCAACGGUAAACUGACAUGGCAACUGAUGAGCGUGUCUUACGGAAAGCUCAUUCCACCCCAGCCCUGUUUCAGCUAGUCCUCAAUUUGGUCCAGUGUCCGAGCCCUGCCUCUGGAGUCAAGUCCCACCUCCUACCUCAUAAGGAGAGACAUAAAUCAAUGGAAUAGAAUCGAGAGUCCAGAAAUAAACUCAUACCUCGAUGAUCAAUUGAUUUUCAACAACGGUGCCAAGACCAUUCAGUGGGGGAAAGAAUCAUAUUUUCAACAAAUGGUGCCAGAUAACGACAUCCAAAGGAGUGCAACUGGGCCCCUAUCUCACACCAUCUACAGAAAUUAAGUCAAAGUGCCUCAAACACUAAGAGCUAAGACUAUAACAUUCUUAGAAGAAUACAGGGAUAUCUCUUUAUGAUCUUGAUUUGGUAAUUGAUUUUUAGAUAACACUAAAAGCACAAGCAACAAUAGGAAAAAAAAAAGUAAAUUUAACCUCAUCAAAAUUUAAAAUUUUUAGGCUGGGUGCAGUGGCUCACACCUCUAAUCCCAGCACUUUGGGAGGCUGAGGCAGAAGGAUCACUUGAGUCCAGGAGUUCGAGACAAGUCUGGCCAACAUGGUGAAACCCCACCUCUACUAAAAAUAUAAAAAUUAGCCAGGAGUGGUGGUAGCUGCCUAUAAUCCCAGCUACUCGGGAGGCUGAGGCCUGAGAAUCACUUGAACCCAGGGGACGCAGGUUGCAAUGAGCUGAGAUCACGCCACUGCACUCCAGCCUGAGGGACAGAGUGAGACUCUGUCUCAAAAACAAACAAACAACAACAACAAAAAAAAAAACCCCACAACUUUUGUGCAUCAGAGGACACAACCAAAUAAUGAAAAGACAACCCACAGACUGGGAGAGAAUGUUUUGCAAAUUAUAUAUCUGAUAAGGGUCUAGUAUCCAAAAUAUAUAAAGAAUUCUUACAACUCAACAAUAAAAGAUAAGCAACUCAGUUUUCAAAUGGGCAAAGGACUUGAAUAGGUAUUUUUCCAAAGAAGAUAUACCAGUGUUCGGUAAGUACAUGAAAAGACGUUCAACAGCAUUAAUCCUUAGGGAGAUGCAGAUCAAAGCCACAGUAAAAUACCACUUCCUACCCAGUAGGAUGAAUAUGAGCAAAAAGAAAAAAAGAAGAAAACAGCAAGUGUUGGUGAUGAUAUGGAGAUUAUCCUCACACAUUGCUGAUGGGAAUGUAAAAUGGUGCAGCUGCUUUAGAAAGCCGUUUGUCAUUUCUUCAAAAAGCUAAACGUAGAAUUCUACUGCAUGACAUAGCAAUUCCACUCCUACAUAUAUACCCAAGAGGAUUUAAAACAAGUGCUCAAAUAAAAUCUUAUACACAAAUGUUCAUAACUACAUUAUUCAUAAGAGACAAAGAGUGGAAACAAGCAAAUGUCCUUCAACUGAUGAAUGGAUAAACCAAAAGUGGUCCAUCCAUACAAUGGGAAAUUAUUCCAUCAUAAAAAGGAAUAGGCUGGGCAUGGAGGCUCACGCCUGUAAUCCCAACAUUUUAGGAGGCCAAGGCGGGCAGAUCACUUGAUGUCAGGAGUUCGAGACCAGCCUGGCUAAUAUGGUGAAACCCCGUCUCUACUAAAAAUACAAAAAAUUAGCUGGGCAUGGUGGCGGGUGCCUGUAAUCCCAGCUACUCAGGAGGCUGAGGCAGGAGAAUUGCUUGAACUUGGGAGGCAGAGGUUGUGGUGAGCCAGGAUUACCCCACUGCACUCCAGCCUGGGCGAUGGAGCGAGACUCUGUCUCAAAACAAACGUACAAAAAAGGAAUGAAAUACUGAUAUAUGCUGCAAUAUGGAUGAACCUUGAAAACAUGCUAAAUGAAAGAAGGCCACAUAUUUUAUGAAUCCAUUUAUAUGAAUUGCCCAGAAUCGGAAAAUCUGUGGAGACAGGAAAUAGAUUAGCGGUUGCCAGGGAGGAGGAGGGAGGAUGGAGAGUGACUGCUCACAGGUACACGGAUUGUUUGGGGUGAUUUGGGAACUAGAUGGUGGUGAUGGUUGUACAACAUUGUGAAUGUACCGAAAACCACUGAAUUAUAUACAUUUUUAAAUGGCUAAAA